AUUCGGCUCUGGCCCCCUGGCCGGCCGGGGGAACCCUGGAACCCCAUGGAGACAGCAGGUCACUUCCUGCUUCCUGGUCCCCACGGUGGCUUCUUGGCCAGGAGUGCAGGGACGCCUCCUCUUUCUCCACGUCGGGCUCAAAAGGGUGGAAACUAAGGCAGAUCGGUGGUGGAGCGGUCAGAUGGGGAUUGAAGAGGAGUGUCAUUCCUCAGGGAAUUGCUGUUCCUGACAAAACCAAACUUGUUUGGGGUUGGAGAACGGGGAUUGAGGAGGUUAGAUGGAGUUGUCCCUUGAUCGGAAACCCAGCCUCUUUAAUUACAGCUGCACCUUGGUCGGAAGCCCAGCCCCUCCGUAACCUAAGCGCUCAAAGCCGGUCUGUCCAGAAUAGGGGUGGUGAAGGGACGGAAAAUUGGAGUUGAGAAAUGUAGUACUCCUUUCACGUAAAGUUUCGGUGUAUAACACUUACAAGUAAUUGCCAACUUAAAAAACAAAAGACUGUUUCGGUAGUUUAGUAAUAAUAUUGGCUUGGGAUGAGGUUUUCUUUGAAGAGAAACGCCUUGUUACAGAGGGAAAAGCCGACCAUACUUGAUAUGAGUAAUAUUCUACUAUGCUACAGUUCUGGAACCUAUAGAGCUUCUCUUAUUCACACAUUUAAUCUUCAUGCUAAAUAGUGCAAAGUAAGAAAAUUGAAGUCAAAGACCAUGGGAGAUACAGCAAAACCUUAUUUCGUGAAGCGCACUAAAGACCGGGGGACUAUGGAUGAUGAUGACUUCAGAAGGGGUCACCCCCAACAAGAUUAUUUAAUAAUAGAUGACCAUGCUAAAGGCCAUGGCAGUAAAAUGGAAAAGGGCCUUCAAAAAAAGAAGAUAACACCAGGGAACUAUGGGAAUACCCCCAGAAAAGGACCAUGUGCUGUUUCCAGCAAUCCAUAUGCAUUUAAAAACCCAAUCUACAGUCAACCCGCUUGGAUGAAUGACAGCCACAAAGAUCAGAGUAAGAGAUGGCUGUCUGAUGAACAUACUGGUAAUUCAGACAACUGGAGAGAAUUCAAACCUGGACCUAGAAUUCCUGUUAUAAACCGACAAAGAAAAGACUCCUUUCAAGAAAAUGAAGAUGGUUAUAGGUGGCAAGACACAAGAGGCUGCAGAACUGUAAGACGACUGUUUCAUAAAGACCUAACAAGCCUAGAAACCACGUCAGAAAUGGAAGCAGGAAGUCCUGAAAACAAGAAGCAGAGGUCCAGACCUAGGAAGCCACGGAAGACUAGAAAUGAGGAAAAUGAGCAGGAUGGAGACUUGGAAGGCCCUGUGAUCGAUGAGUCUGUACUUUCAACGAAGGAGCUGCUAGGCUUACAGCAGGCUGAGGAGAGACUGAAGAGAGACUGCAUUGACAGGCUAAAAAGGCGACCACGAAACUACCCUACAGCAAAGUACACCUGCAGACUCUGUGAUGUUUUAAUUGAAUCCAUUGCAUUUGCCCAUAAGCAUAUCAAGGAAAAGAGGCACAAGAAAAACAUUAAGGAGAAGCAAGAGGAAGAGUUGCUCACUACGUUACCCCCACCAACACCCUCCCAGAUAAAUGCAGUUGGCAUUGCCAUUGACAAAGUGGUACAGGAAUUUGGCUUACACAAUGAGAACUUGGAACAGAGGCUGGAAAUUAAACGUAUCAUGGAAAAUGUGUUCCAACACAAGUUACCAGAUUGUUCCCUAAGAUUAUAUGGGUCAUCCUGUAGCAGAUUGGGUUUCAAAAAUUCGGAUGUAAACAUUGACAUCCAGUUUCCAGCCAUUAUGUCUCAGCCAGAUGUCCUCUUACUUGUUCAAGAAUGUUUAAAGAACAGUGACUCCUUUAUUGAUGUUGAUGCAGACUUCCAUGCUAGGGUGCCAGUGGUGGUGUGCAGAGAAAAGCAAAGUGGUCUUCUGUGUAAAGUGAGCGCAGGAAAUGAAAAUGCUUGUCUGACAACAAAGCAUUUAACUGCCCUUGGAAAACUAGAACCAAAGCUGGUUCCUUUGGUGAUUGCAUUUAGGUACUGGGCAAAGCUUUGCAGUAUAGAUCGCCCUGAAGAAGGAGGUCUGCCACCUUAUGUGUUUGCCCUGAUGGCCAUUUUCUUUCUUCAGCAGAGGAAAGAACCCCUUUUGCCUGUAUAUCUAGGAUCAUGGAUUGAAGGAUUCUCAUUAAGCAAACUAGGGAAUUUCAACCUUCAAGACAUUGAAAAAGAUGUUGUGAUCUGGGAACAUACUGACAGUGCUGCAGGGGACACAGGCAUAACAAAAGAAGAGGCACCAAGAGAAACGCCGAUUAAAAGGGGACAGGUGUCAUUAAUAUUGGAUGUGAAACACCAGCCUUCAGUACCAGUUGGGCAGCUCUGGGUGGAAUUGCUGCGGUUCUAUGCUUUAGAAUUUAAUUUGGCUGAUUUAGUGAUAAGUAUUCGUGUCAAAGAAUUGGUAUCUCGGGAAUUGAAGGAUUGGCCCAAAAAGCGCAUUGCCAUUGAAGAUCCCUACUCUGUUAAAAGAAAUGUGGCAAGAACCCUAAAUAGUCAACCUGUGUUUGAAUAUAUACUUCAUUGUUUAAGGACAACAUACAAGUAUUUUGCUCUUCCACACAAAAUUACAAAAUCCAGCCUUCUAAAGCCUCUGAAUGCAAUUACAUGUAUUUCAGAACAUUCUAAAGAAGUAAUAAAUCAUCAUCCAGAUGUACAAACAAAAGAUGAUAAGCUCAAAAACUCAGUUUUGGCCCAAGGUCCUGGUGCUACCAGUUCAGCUGCAAAUACCUGUAAGGUACAGCCACUUACUCUUAAAGAGACUGCUGAAAGUUUUGGAAGCCCACCAAAAGAAGAAAUGGGAAAUGAACACAUCAGUGUCCACCCUGAAAACUCAGACUGUAUCCAAGCAGAUGUUAACUCUGAUGAUUACAAGGGUGAUAAAGUAUACCAUCCAGAAACAGGAAGGAAAAACGAGAAAGAGAAAGUUGGAAGGAAGGGCAAGCAUCUGUUGACUGUUGAUCAGAAACGUGGAGAGCAUGUUGUCUGUGGCAGCACACGUAAUAAUGAGUCAGAGAGCACUUUGGAUUUAGAAGGCUUCCAAAAUCCCACAGCUAAAGAGUGUGAGGGACUUGCCACUUUAGAUAACAAGGCUGAUCUUGAUGGAGAAAGUACAGAAGGUACUGAGGAACUAGAAGACUCUCUAAACCACUUUACCCACUCAGUACAGGGCCAGACAUCAGAAAUGAUUCCCUCUGAUGAAGAGGAGGAGGACGACGAAGAAGAGGAGGAGGAAGAAGAACCUAGGCUCACCAUUAACCAAAGGGAAGAUGAAGAUGGCAUGGCUAAUGAAGAUGAGUUAGACAACACCUACACUGGGUCAGGGGAUGAGGACGCCCUAUCUGAAGAGGAUGAUGAGUUAGGCGAAGCUGCUAAGUAUGAAGACGUGAAAGAAUGUGGAAAACAUGUAGAAAGAGCUCUCCUAGUGGAACUUAAUAAAAUAAGUCUCAAGGAAGAAAAUGUAUGUGAAGAAAAAAAUUCACCUGUGGAUCAGUCUGAUUUUUUUUAUGAAUUCAGUAAACUUAUCUUCACCAAAGGCAAGUCUCCUACGGUAGUGUGCAGCUUAUGCAAACGAGAGGGUCAUCUAAAGAAGGACUGUCCUGAAGACUUCAAAAGAAUCCAGCUAGAACCUCUGCCACCAUUAACACCCAAGUUUUUAAAUAUCUUAGAUCAAGUCUGUAUCCAGUGUUAUAAGGAUUUUUCUCCAACAAUUAUAGAAGAUCAGGCUCGUGAACAUAUUCGGCAAAACCUAGAAAGUUUCAUAAGACAGGACUUUCCAGGAACUAAAUUGAGCCUGUUUGGCUCCUCCAAAAAUGGAUUUGGGUUCAAACAGAGUGACCUUGACGUCUGUAUGACAAUUAAUGGACUUGAAACUGCUGAGGGAUUGGACUGUGUCAGAACUAUUGAAGAAUUAGCAAGAGUCCUCAGAAAACAUUCAGGUCUGAGAAACAUCUUACCUAUUACAACAGCAAAGGUGCCAAUUGUGAAGUUCUUCCAUUUGAGAAGUGGUCUGGAAGUAGAUAUCAGUUUGUAUAACACAUUGGCCCUUCAUAACACAAGGCUUUUAUCUGCUUAUUCCGCCAUUGAUCCCAGAGUGAAGUAUUUGUGCUAUACCAUGAAAGUAUUUACAAAGAUGUGUGAUAUUGGUGAUGCAUCUAGAGGCAGCUUAUCAUCGUAUGCAUAUACUCUUAUGGUGCUAUAUUUUCUCCAGCAGAGGAAUCCACCAGUCAUUCCUGUCCUUCAAGAGAUAUACAAAGGUGAAAAGAAACCUGAAAUAUUUGUUGAUGGCUGGAAUAUUUAUUUUUUUGAUCAAAUAGAUGAACUGCCUACCUAUUGGUCAGAAUGUGGAAAAAAUACAGAAUCUGUUGGGCAGUUAUGGUUGGGCCUUCUUCGUUUCUACACAGAGGAAUUUGAUUUUAAAGAACAUGUUAUUAGCAUCAGGAGAAAAAGUCUGCUUACAACUUUUAAGAAACAGUGGACCUCAAAAUACAUUGUUAUUGAAGAUCCCUUUGAUUUGAAUCAUAAUCUUGGAGCUGGAUUAUCAAGGAAAAUGACAAAUUUUAUAAUGAAGGCUUUUAUCAAUGGUAGAAGAGUAUUUGGUAUUCCUGUCAAGGGAUUUCCAAAGGACUACCCCUCAAAAAUGGAAUACUUUUUUGAUCCAGAUGUGUUAACUGAAGGAGAGCUGGCCCCAAAUGAUAGAUGUUGUCGAAUUUGUGGAAAAAUCGGACACUUCAUGAAGGACUGUCCUAUGAGGAGAAAAGUAAGACGGCGGCGAGAUCAGGAAGAUGCCCUGAACCAAAGAUACCCUGAGAACAAGGAAAAAAGAAGCAAAGAGGACAAAGAAAUUCACAACAAGUACACAGAAAGGGAGGUGUCAACAAAAGAAGAUAAGCCCAUACAGUGCACACCUCAGAAAGCCAAGCCAAUGCGGGCAGCUGCUGACCUGGGGAGGGAGAAGAUCCUCAGGCCACCAGUAGAAAAAUGGAAGAGACAGGAUGACAAAGACUUAAGAGAAAAACGUUGUUUUAUUUGUGGAAGAGAAGGGCACAUUAAAAAGGAAUGCCCACAGUUUAAAGGCUCUUCAGGAAUGUCUAAAUCAGAUUGUAUGUUUGGAUCGCCCUCACCUGUCCCAUUGAAACCAACUGGUUUAUUUGUUCAGGCAGUGCUUUUACAUGAAGACAAAAAGAAACAAAAAACAACAAUAUUUUUGAGUCCCCAGUCAGGUAUGUGGGUUUUAAAAAAAACAAAUGUGUGUUAUUUUAUUUACUGCAUACUUUACCACAUGCCUUUUGAGACUUUUUCUCCAAAUAUGUGCUUUUAACAGGGAUUGGACAUCAGAAUCACUUGGGGGAACUUUAAAACAUAUAGUUGCCCAUCCUCUACCUUUAUUUCCUAAAGCUAAUUCUUCAGUGGUUAAGCAUGGGCCUGUGUGUUUUGUAAAUUCCAAGUGAUGUUUAUACCACCCAUGAGUGGCAACCAGAGUCUUCAAUUAUUUGUUCCAGUCCCGUGCUUUUUGUUGCUGCUGUCUUGCCAGCAGUGUUUUCUCCUCCUGGAGAGUAUUUGCCACACACAAAGUAAGGAAAAAAACUAAUCUCUAGCCUGAACUCCACUGUUACCUCUCAGCUACUUCAUUUAUUCAUUCUUUCAACAAAUAGCUAUCCAGCCUCUCCCCUCCCUUUCCAAGUUCAGGACACCAGCCUCAACACUGAAGAUACAGCAGUGAACAAGCAAAGCCCCUUCUCUCAUUUACUCUGCAUCCUUUUCAGAAGAGGUAGACAAUAAAGAGAUACAGAAAUAAUAUGUCAUGUGGUGGCAAAUGCUAGGAAGAAAUAACAAAACAAGAAAAGGGAAAGAGAAUGGUUGGCUAAGGAGGCAGCAUCUCUGGUAAAGUAACAUUUAAGCAAAGAAUCAAAUGAAACAAAGGGGCCAGUCGGGGGAAAUUGGUGUUAGACUGGUAAACUCAGAGAUGGAAACAGGUGUUGUCCUGCAGCAUCACUGAGGCAGUGUGGCAGGAGUGGAACAGGAUUGGAAACUCGAGAGACAGAAGAAAUUUGAAAAAAAAAAAAAAGUGGAGCAGGCAGAAGGGUGAGUGAGUGGUAGAGGUGAAGUCAGAGGGUGGAUAGAUCUGGGUUAUGAAGCGCCUUCAGCAGUGGUAGGUACCGUUUUUGUUGGUUUUUUUCUCCCUCAAAGUGAAAUGAGAGACUAUUGUAGGGUUUUGAGCCAAGGAGUGAUAUUAUCUGAAUUCUGUUUUAAAAGGUUCAUUAUGGCUCCUGUGUGGAGGCAGGGUAGCUACUUAGAAACCAAGCCAUCUCAGCCUCCCGAUUUGUAGAGAUGUGGUCUCACUAUGUUGCCCAGACUGGUCUUGAACUCCUGGCCUCAUGUGAUCCUCCCACCUUGGCCUCCCAAAAUACUAAAAUGAUAGAUAUGAGCCGCCACACCUGGCCAUAAGCUUCAGCCUUGAGCAGAUACUUUCUAAACACUUUAUAUAGGGAAAAAAAACUAAUUCUUGCGUAGCCAAGGUGUUCAUUUUGCCGAGAAUAACGUAGCAUAGUGUUUACAAUUACGUGGGUGUAAUUUCUAGCUUUGUGAUCCUGAGAGACUGCCUUAUCCUCCAUAUGCCUCAGUUUUCUCAUGUGUAAAAAGGGGGUAAUAAUAAUACCUGACAGGGAUGUUGAGAAAUCCAUGUAAAAGUACUUAGAACAGCGCCUGCAUAUAGUGAGAGCAGAGAAAAGGGAAAAGGUUCGUGGUGGUGAUUGCAUUGAUGUUAUUAUUCCUUCAGGGUAUCACCAAGUCUUCCAGUGCCAGCAUUGUUCAGUUGAGAGAGAAAUAUAGAUGCUAGGCAUACACCUAGAAAUAGCAUUGACAGUAAGUUACGAUUUCUGUAAUUAUCUUCUUAGUAAAAAACCUACAUAUUUAUAAAUCUUUUGAGCAACUGGAAAAAAAGUAUUAACUUAAAUUUACUACAGGAAAAAUGUAUUGCAAUAAUUAUGUUACUUUAUACCAGAAAAAAGAAAACAUUUAUAGGUGGUUAAAAUCGAUCCUAUCCAAUAAAUCAGACUCUUCCAAAUAAGUAUAUGUCAGAUGAUAUAACUGUCUAGUUUAUCUGUGAUAUAUGUAUCCAAAUUAUCUAUGUUGUUAUAAAUGUGAACUGUAUCUCACCUGUAAGUGGUGUUAAUUUCCCCACAGCUCUUCCUUUCCAUAGUAUUAAGUAUGUCUUUGGCCCACUUGUAGUUUCUCAAGAAAGCAUGUUGAUACGGACAGCCCCUACUCUCAUAUAUGGUGUAUUGACCUUAGGCAAGAGAUGUGGUUUCUCUGAGCUCCAGAUAUGUCAUCUAUAAAAUUGGUGUUAACACCGUUUAUCUCAUAGGGUGCUAAGAAGAUUAAAGUACUGCCCAGAGUAGGCACUCAGUCAAGUUCUCUUUCCUCUCCUGAUACCUACCCCCAUCCUUUCCUCUAGGUUGCAUAUAGUUCUUUACUCCCAAAGGAGAUCACAGUAGAUAGAAAAUCCCAUGAAUGUCCUUGCUCUUCGUUGUUACCUCCCUCCCCCUCUAUCCCCCACACAUAAUGCCUUAGAUAUUCAGUAGGUUUUAUUGAUUAGAGGUGAACUUAUUUGGAAGGAAUAAAAAGACAAAGCAGGAGAAUGGUCAAGAACAUGAGUUUUAGAGUGAGACACUUGAGUUUGAAAUCCAGCCCAACCAUUUACUAGUUGUGUGACCUCUAUCAAGUUAUGCAACCUCUCUGUGCCUCAGUUUCCUUUUUGGCAAAUUGGUGCUAACACCUCACAGGACUAUUGUAAGGAUUAAGUUCAUGUAGAUAAAGCACUUAACACAGCAUCCGACACAUCUCAUCACUCAAUAAAUUAUCACUGCCCUUUGUUACUGUGGUUAACAAACACUUGCUGUAAUUUCUCUCUUCUAACUUAUAGGACAAACAAAUAAUGGAAAUUUUUAACAUAAGUAUGUAGAGAUUGUGGUACCACAGUGAUAAACUGAUUUUUAUGCUUAAGUUAAUGACUCUGGUUUAUGUAUGACAAUUUAUUCAGUAUGAGAAUCUCAGAAAACUAAUGUUUUUUUCUAUUCCUUAACCUUCCUACCCUUUUUUUGGUAAAGAAAAUUACCGAAAAAACAAAAAACAAAAAAAAAACUACCUCUGUCUAUUUAUUUAUUCCAUUUUAAUCUCAUGGCUUGAAAUCUGAAAAAUUGGAGUUGCUGUAAGAGAUUGGUGGAUGUCUUUUUGCCCUCAUGGUGAUGUAUUCUUUUACAGCUUUUAUCAUUGACCAGAAUUUUAAGGCCUGCUUAUUUUAAAAAACGAAAACCAGUGUUCUUUAUGAUAAUAAGCUUAAAAUAAUAGAAAUACUUUUUAAAAUAGUAUGGGGAGAGCUCAUUGUCAGUGAAUAUAGAUCAUUCUUGUUGAUACCCUUCUUUGAAUAUUCUAGUGUAUUAAUAUACCAUUGUUUAUUUAAUCAUGUCUUAUUAAUGGACUGGCUGUUUUCACAUAUUUGAUAUAUCAAGUGUCUUCACAACUUGUGCUUGCAUAUUCUUUCCCAAAAUAUUGAAAGUCCAUAUAUUUCCUUGUACAUUUUUAAAGUUGAUAUCUAAAUCUUUCAUUGUAGUUGCAAAGCAUGUAAUUUCUUGGGGGAGGGGGGCUGUAAAUAUUGACAUUUUAAAAUAAAACUUUUAAAUCAGCCUUAAA